ACUGUUACCAAGGAGAUGGAUUGCCUUCCAAAGGCAAAUAUGAUGAUGAAGAAUUCCCACCCCUCCCCCAGCCCCCGCCUUUGGCUGCUCUUGUGUUCAAAGAAUGUCACUGUACCCAACUGUUUUCCUUGCAAGGAAUAGGGACGAAAGUACCUUGUCUUAAACUUUUGUGGUUAGAGAAGCCCACAGCCCUUAGGGAAACAUUGCAUUUUUAAAAAAUGACUUUAAAUCCGUGCUGUUGAUACUUAUGUCUAAUGCCAGUCAUUGGUCUGGGAUCUGUGUGCAGAGUUGCCUUCUGUCUGGUGAGACUGGAGUGGGUGCGGGUCAGAUUCCGUAACCUCGUGGAGAGAGGAUAAAAACUAGAUUGAAAGAAGAACAUCAGAGGGGAUCUGUUCCCUCUUAAAUCCCUGGAAGCUCCAGAGGCCGUGAGAGUUGAGAUGAGAGAAACUAUUCUGUGGUACCUUUUAUAUGAAUGAGGUAUUUGUUUACAACAAUAUCCAGAUAAUUUUCUUUUUACAGUAAUGGCUACAAUUUUGCCCCAUCCUGUUAUCAUUGGUGAUGAAGGCUAUAAACAGAUGUGUGGAAGUUGAUGUUUUUCAGAUUUCGUUUUCAUUUUAUUCUGAGCAUUCUUUAACAGAGCUGUACCCAGUUAGCAGGAUUUACCUUGUUUAAAGUUUGGUCUCCUUUUAUUUUUCUGGUCCUUAAUUUUAGUGGAGAGGUCCAUGCGAAGUCAAUUUGCUGAGAUCUGCCAGUAGAUGGAGGAAAGAAAAAGUACAGUAAGUCCUCACUUAACAUUGUCGGUAGGUUCUUGGAAACUGUGGCUUUAAGUAAAAUGGAUUCUUGAAUAAUGUCAUUUUGUUCAACGUAGUUUUUAUUGUAAUGUUGAGGACAAAAAAAUUGGUUUUGUUAUGUGUUGUUUUACUUAAAGUUGCAGUUUCCAAGAACCUAUCGACGAUGUUAAGCGGGGAUUCCAUGUAAUUGUAAUCGUCAGUUGAAGUGGCUCUGGAGUGUUUUUGGGAUUGAAGUUUUAUUGAUGAAAAAGUAGGCAUUGGCAAAUUUUUUUUUUUAACAGCUGUAUUGAAAUACAAUGCACAUACUAGGGCACUGGAAAUUUAGAAUUAGCUCAGGGACACUAGAGUAGACAGUAGACCAAGUCUGGGACUCUGAUGAGAGGCCCAUUGACAUUAUUUGUUUGUUUAAAUUAGGAGGCCCAAACCUGAGUUAGAUUUCAUCCUCUCCAAACCUCAGUUUCCUCACCUGUAAAGUAGAGAAAAUAAUACUUGGGCCUACCCCAUAGGGCUCAUUCAAGGAUUCAGUAAGCCUCUAGUCCAUAUUAAGUGUUUUGGGGCCAUGCAGGGCCAACUGAAGUUCCAGUGUGUAGUGGCGGGGAGAUACCCCUUAAUCCAGCCUCAUGCGCAGACUGUCAUAAAGUAUGGGAACCUUAUCUUUCUGGUCUGCAUAGUUUCUUCUGGUGAAAGAAUGGUUAAUUGAACUGAAAGUACAUUGUGUCUUGUGUUUGGGAAAUAAAAUAGUGAUCUGAGAUGCCAAUUAAAUCUAGUGUUGCCAGAUAAAAUAUGGGACACCCAGUAAAAUUUGAACUUCAGAUAAAUAAUGAAAAAUUUUCAGAAUAAAUAUGUCCCAAUAUAAUUGUAGUUUACCUUAAAUUUAACUAGUUGUUCUGCAUUUUUAUUGGUGAAGUCUGGCACCUCUAAUUUUGUCUCAUUGUUUCCCCAUUUGGAAUCUUUUGGCUGCCUUUAUGAUAGCUGAAAAUGAGUUGAGGAAUUUCAAAUAGGAUGCAGAGGUAUGAUUUUAUUUGCAUCUGCCCCAUAGCUCCUGUCCUUUGUUGUUGCUAAUAGAAACCUGGCCUUUCACGAAAGGUCCCGUCAUCUAUUAAAACACUGGUUGCAUAGCAGCCAAACAUUUUUGUUGAGAAAUAAGCCGGACGGAAAUCUCUGUGAUGACACUUCCUUCAACCUCACGCUAUUGCCGAACAUGCGACAAGGAGGAUGUUGGGAAUGGAAUCAUAAGAAUCCUCCUGCAGCACGUCAGCAGUUCACCCUGGAGCAGUUAGAGGUCAGCAGGCAGGGACUCUGGUGGCAUCUGGGGAUGUGUUCUUGGGCUUUAAUAGCAGGUAGGAAGCCUUAUCUGUGGAGGAGUCCAGCAGUGAACAUCCCAUUCUGCAUGCCAAGGGAACGCACAAAUAGGCAACAUACAAAAACAAAAGAAGUCAAAGGCCUGGUCCUUGAUCACUGAGGAGUGUAUAGUUCCAGAGAGGGAUAGGACCAGCAGGUAUUUACACAACACUUCCUUUGUGACUUUGUAUCAGCACUGGUAGGUGCUUUCCACGCACUGUCAUAGUAAUCCUUAACAGCAGCCCUGUGAACAAGAUCCUGUUAUUAUUCCCAUUUUCCACAUGAGGAGACUGAAGCUUAGGCUGUGGGAUGGAGCCUGCAGCCGUAAAGUCAGCCUGACCUAAAAGUUCCUGUUCUGUCUCUACUCCUUAUCAAAUAUUGCAAGUAUAGGUUGAAUCAUAUGAAAUUGCCAGUAUGUAACAAUUUUGACCUACAAAAAACGACAGUUUUAUAUGGUUCAACUUCAUCCAAAGAACGAGACCCAAUAUUAUAUACACACACAUAUAUAUAUUACAAAUAACUUGCUAUUCCGUAACUAUUACACAUAACUUGCCGAGGCUGACUAGGGUGAAUGAAAUAUGUGGACCUAGUUUUGGUCUAACCAGGGAUGCUUCUGGGAAGCUAGUUUUCAUUCAUUCACUCACCCACUCACUCAUUGGCUCACUCACUGAAUGGAAACUUACUGAAUUCUUCCAAGCAUAUUAUUAAGCAUAGGUUUGAACAGAUUUUAUUUUUUAUUUUUAUUUUUUUGAGACCGAGUCUCACUGUGUUGCCCAGGCUGGAGUGCAAUGGUGUGAUCUCGGCCCACUGCAACCUCUGCCUCCUGGGUUCAAGCAAUUCUCGUGCCUCAGCCUCCCGAGUAGCUGGGAAUACAGGCAUGUGCCACCACACCCAGCUAAUUUUUGUAUUUUUAGUAGAGACGGGGUUUCACCAUGUUGCCUAGGCUGGUCUCAAACUCCUGACCUCAGGUGAUCCACCUGCCUUGGCUUCCCGAAGUUCUGGGAUUACAGGCAUGAGCCACCAUGCCCGGGCUGAACAGAUUUUUUUUUUUAAACUUUUUAUUCAGAAAAAUUUCCUUCCUGCUCAUUUGUAGUGAAUUCUGCUCUCACCAUCAUGCAACCACUAAUCUGUGUUUUGUAUGUGGGCCAUUUCUGGCCAUCUUGUAUGAAUGGAAUCAUUCAACGUAUGAUUGUUUGUGUCUUGCUUCUUUCACUUAGCAUAAUGUUUUUCGGGUCCAUUCAUGUUGAAGCAUGUGUCACGAGCUUAUUCCUUUUUAUUGCUGAAUAGUAGUCCAUCAUGUGGCUAUACCACAUUUUCUUUUUCUUUUUCUUUUUUUCCUUUCUUUUCUUUUUUUUUUUUUUGAGAUGGAGUUUCACCCUUUUCGCCAGGCUGGAGUGCAGUGGCGCAAUCUCGGCUCACUGCAACCUCCGCCUCUCGGGUUCAAGCAGUUCUCCUGCUUCAGCCUCCCAAGUAGCUGGGAUUACAAGCAUGUGCCACCACACCUGGCUAAUUUUGUAUUUUUGGUAGAUGUGCGGUUUUGCCAUGUUGGUCAGGCUGUUCUCGAAGUCCUGACCGCAGGUGAACCACCCGUCUUUGCCUCCCAAAGUGCUGGGAUUACAGGUGUGACCCACCACGCCUGGCCCACAUUUAGUUUUUCUAUUCUCCAGUUCAUAGACAUUUGGAUCAUUUUUACUUUUUGGCUAUUAUGUAUGUUGCUACUAUGAAAUUUUUGUACAAGUUUUUGUGUGGAUGUAUCAUUUCUCUUGGGUAGGUAACUAGGAGUGGAAUUGCUAGGUCAUGUGGUAAGUUUGUAUUUUACUUUUAGCAGGUUUUUGAGGAGGGAGAGCGAAAAAUGAGUUUAUAUGAAGGCCCAAAAGUGUGACUGAGGUUUGGAAUAGCUAAUGAGGCAGCUGUAACCUGGAAUGAAGUACCAGAACCCAGAAAGAUGAGCUGGACAGAUUUUAGUAGGAAGGUUAAAGGUGCUCUGGAGUUAGCCAGUGAUCCUGCUGCCUCUCCUUCUCUAUGAAGCCAGUGUUCCUUUCUUUGCAUAUUUGGUAGGGUGGGUAAAAGGCUCCUCUUUCUGUUGCUGAUUUUGGACCAGGAAUGUCAUUUUUUAACCUUCCAGUGGCAAUAGUCCUUAACCCGGAAGUAGCAAUGCUCCCCCUUCUAGAGCAUCAAUUCCCUAAUGUGGAAAUCCAGUCCCACAGUUUUCUCUGAGAAAAAUGUGGACAGUGUAAUAUAAUGGGUUAUUCAUAAGCCUAAAUUUAUAUAAUGCAAAGGUGUGUGUCUUAUUCUUGGAGUGUAUCUUUCUUACUGUUUUGGAAUAAUGAAGACUUUUUGUUGUUGUUGUCGGAGACAGAGUCUUGCUGUUUUGCCCAGGCUGGAAUGCAAGGCACAAAGACGGCUCACUGGAGCCUUGACCUUCUGAGCUCAAGUGAUCCUCCUGCUUCAGCCUCCCAAGGAGCUGGGACCACGGGCAUGUGCCACCAGGCCCAUGUAUUUUUUUAUUUUUAUUUUUUGUAGAAACGGAAUCUCACUAUGUUGCUCAGGCUGGUCUUGAACUUUUGGGCUCAAGCAAUCCUCCUGCCUGGGAUUACAGUGCUGGGAUUACAGGCCUGAGCCAUUGUGCUGGCCAUGACAACUUUUUAAUUCAGUGAUGUUAAUAUAUGUUUUUUAACGGUUGUACAUGGCAUAAUAAGUUAUAGGCAAUGAAAUGUGUGUGUGUGUGUGUGUGUGUGUGUGUGUGUGUUUAGUUUAAGUUGGUUGUUGAAAUUCCCAAAUCUGGGGACUACUUCUCCAAAGAAAGUUUUGGGAAGGCAUUAGUUAACAUCUUUGUAUUUUGCCUUCUUCCGUAUUUUCUUACAUUAUUGUGUAGUGUGGGCAUCUAGAGUGAUGCCUGGACGACAUCACAGUGAAAGAUUAGUGCAACGAAGAAAAGACAAUCCCAGUUAUGUACCCCCCCACUACUUAGACAUCUAACUCUGUGUUAAUAUAUGCAGUUGAUGGGCACAUGUCAUCUUAAAUCCUUUUGGUAGUACAAAGAAGCCAGAACUAAGUUUAGUUUGGAUUUCUUACGCAUAUUUGGAACUAACCAGCAGUUGACUCAUUUCAGGAUAAGCAGUUGUUUUCUAUGGAUAUUCUGCUGAGGUUGGAGGCUCUGCACCAACUGUAUGUGGUGAGGGCUUUGAUAUAGAACAGCAGCACUGGAUCCAAAGUGUGAAGGGAGCCCUCAGGCUUGCUAUACUGUGCCCGUCCUCAAGGUUGGGGCUAGGGAGAGGGAUUUUUCUGUAACAUGAUCCUACAGUACACAUAGCCACAUUCUCCAGUUAAUAAUGACAACCGUGAUAAUGGUUGAAAUUAAUCACAGUGAAAUUAAGGCAUGAAAUUAAUAACAGUGAAUGCAUUGAGCCAACAUCAUGCUAAAUGCUUUCAGGCAUGAUGCAAUUUGAUCCUAGCAACAGUUGUGUUAGACAGGUAUGGUUAUUCCUUUUUUGUGAGAAGCAACUUAGGGGCAGUAGUGUUUGGUAAAUUGCACACUUACCUUGCCACUGACUGAAUGAGAGAUGUAGAGCCCAUUGCCAGAAGGGGCCAAGCCAGGGUUCAAACCUAACCUGUUCUUUUAAAACCAUGAGCCUCUCAGAUCAGCAGUUUCUACACCAGAUUGUAUUCCCAGAGGCCCAGCGCUUCAGUUCAGCUGUGCUGCUGAGGUCUUGUGUGUGAAAAGGGAACUGGGAAUGGAUUCUGCAGGCCAUGCUUAGCAAAACCUCCCUGAGGCAGCCCACGGCUCUGGUGUAUCCAGCACACUUUAUUGCUGCCCCUCUGUCUACAGACGGCUCUAUUGAUUCAGCCUUGGGAAGUCUUUGCCCCCUGCCCUCUUCACCCUUUUUGUUGAUACAUUCCCAGAAUGUUCAAGUUCACACCCAUGUUGCAACCCUGGCUCCUAAGCCUGAGGACAGGAUGUGAGUGCCUGCCCUGGUGCUCAUGGGUAUCAGCGGGACAGAGAUUUGUGCUGAGCUGCGUGCUGCUGGCUUCCCCCUUGCCUGUCCUUGGGAACUGGGGACUUUACCCGCUGUCUUUAUGCAGUUCUUACAGGCCAUAUUUUAAUGCUGUGUCAUCUCUUAGAAAGAUGGGUUGAAAAGGAUAAACUGGAAGCUUCUAUUCAUUUCUCUUUUAUUUUUAAGAAUGUUGUAUUUUGGCAGGGUGUGGUGGCUCACGCCUGUAAUCCCAGCACUUUGGGAGGCCGAGGCGGGCGGAUCACGAGGUCAGGAGAUCGAAACCAUCCUGGCUAAUACGGUGAAACCCCGUUUCUACUAAAAAUACAAAAAAUUAGCCAGGCGUGGUAGUGGGUGCCUGUAGUCCCAGCUACUCGGGAGGCUGAGGCGGGAGAAUGGCAUGAACCCGGGAGGCAGAGCUUGCAGCGAGCUGAGAUCACACCACUGCACUCCAGCCUGGGCAACAGAGUGAGACAUUGUCUCGGAAAAAAAAAAAAAAAAAAAAAAAAAAAAAAAAAAAAAAAAUGUUGUAUUUUAGGAGAACAUUGAUCCGAAAGGUGAUUUGCAUGUCUUUUCUGCUUGUUAAACUCAGCAUAGUUUGAGGUGGGGAAAUCCCAAUCAUCUAAUUGGUGUCAAAUUUUGUUUAGUAGUAAUUUCUGCAUUCCCUUUUCUUUCCUUUCCUCCUCUCCUCUUUUUUUUUUCUCAUCAGUUUAACAUUUGCCAUAGUUUAUGCUUAGCAACCUGUGAGAUACGGCUAGUGUCACUCACUUUUGGUAACACGGAGUCACCAAGGUACAGAAUAACUAAGUGGGGUAUGCAGGGUCUGGCCAGAAAUACAAUCUUUUGAUUGCUAGCCCAGCUGCUUUCCUUGUUAUCACUUUGUGGAGCAGGCUGGACAUUGACAAUGAGUUCUGAGACUGAGUGGAAUGGGAGACCCCUCCCAGCUGGUGGUCGAGCUGCCUAGAGCAUGGUCCAUCUGUUUGGGACUAGGGUUGAGCUCCAAGAUGGACCAAUCAACCCCACCAAGAAAGAAACCCCUUCUAUCACCGCGGAGUGUACCAUAGCUCCUGUCAGCCGCUCUGGAAGUUUUUGCCACCAGAAGAGAGAUGCAGAGCAUCUUUUCUUACCACAGCUGAACUGAGAACAUAUGUUUCAUCCAUAUAUGGCACCUUACUUAUUAAGCUUGUGUCCUUGUCCUUUCUAAUACUCUGGCACCUUGCCCAUCAGAUGGCUGCCCCUUUUUAUAAGAUAAGUGCCUGUAUGGCUGGCUGUUCUGAUUUUAAGUCAUGAGCUUUGACUUUUAUCAGAAAUUUACAGCUUGGUUUUCAAAGGACUUAGUUGAGUGCAACUGCAUGAAAUGGUAGUGUUAAAUUUUAUACUGUAGAAAUGUUGAAAUGGAACUCUAUAAAAUGUGCGUUUUCAGUGUCUUUUUUGAAUGGUUUUAUUUGUGUGUUUUAUCAGUCUUAGACAUUUUUAUUACUCAAGUAAUCUGUUCAUUGUAGAAUGAUUAGAAAAUACAGAUAAGCAAAGAGAGAGAGGAAAAGAAAAGAAAAAAAUAUAGGUCUACUGUAAAUAAAAGUUCCCCAAGAGAGAAGCCAGGAUGUGAAGGACUUUGAGCUUCUUAGAAGAAGGGGUCAGAUCAGCUGGUGCAAUUCUGCAUUCCCAGCAGCACUCUGUUCUUCCUGUUUUGGACACUAGCAAUCAAGACAGAAGUUGGGGUGUCUGAAUAUGUCCUGGAGAAAGUCAAGAUGGCUUUUGGUUUGCUGCCCCAGGCAGUGAGUCCCGGUGGUUCAGGGGCCAAAAGUCCUGCAGUUAAUCCACCACCUGCAAGGGAUGGCUGUGAAAAGAGAAAAAUAGUCCUCCUUUGGAGUCCCAUUAUUUAUACAGUUGCUAGCUUUCAAGCAGAUAGAGAGAAAAUAAUCUUACAGUCAUGCUUUCCCUCCUCUUAACUUCUGCCAGUCCUGCUGGAGCCAUCCACUCCUUCAUUCAUCUGUCCAUCCAUCCAUCCAUCCAAUCACUCAUUCAUUCAUUCAUCCACUUAGUGGCUCACUUCAUUCAUCCAUUCAAUACCAAUUUACUGUGUACCUGCUGAGCACUAAACACUGUUGCAUUUGGUUCUGGGAAUACAGCAUGAAUAAGAUAAGGCCCUUCUCUCAUGGAUCUUACAUUGGACUGGUGCAGGUUUUAGUAUCAUUGCUUCCCUUUCAGCCUUACCUUUCUACAGCUGUGGAUAAGAUGCCAUGAAUUUGCGAGUAAAAGUGUUUAUCUCUCCCUGGAGCAGACUAGACCCCUAGGCUCUGUCCUAGAGCACAACUCACCCUUAGCUGCCCUGCAACCUGAUCAUCUCCAACAGGGAAGGUGAAGAGAAGGCAGUAUUUGGCUGAUGAAUUCUUCUCAAAAUGAUACUUUAGUUUUGUCUGGGAGGGGCAGGGGAACAGAUCACAGAGGGAGGGGUUCUUGGCUUUAUCAGAGAAAGAAGGCCUCAUUGUGUGUUGUUGUUGGAACAGGUCCCAGAGACCUCAGUACAAUUCUUUGGACAGGGCUGAGCUAAGCUACCAUGUAUACAAUAAUAGUCGAAAGAAUAGUGUGGAAUUUAGGGUAGUAUCAAAGAGAGCUCUGUGUUACAGCUGUCUUCAGGCAGAGGGCAUGACUUCAGCCCCAGGUCAAGUCCUGUUGUUAACUUCAUAAUAUUUUAAUGAACAUGCCUUUUUGUGUCUGUUCCUCUCCCCUCUCCCCCAUCUCUUUCUUUUUUGUGUGUGUAGUCAUUUAUUAAGGGAUUUUGAUAGAAAAUUUAAAACUUAAUCUCUGUAAACUCUUCCUUUUGAACUAUGGCAUACCUGAGUGGACAGGCAAGUUGCAGGGAUGGGGACAUUUGACACAGAGAACUUAGGAAGUUCCAGGAAACCAGUAUUUCUGAAACUGUAGUCAAUUCUGUUUUGAUUUUUUGCUACAUUGAUGUAAUACCUAUUUCAUUGUUGACCUAAUAUUGUUCUUUAAGUGGGAGUGCUUGUUCUUUUUGAAGGGACACUCUUCGUUUAAUAAAGAACAAGUAUAAUUCGCCCAAAAUAGUAAGUAACCAUAAGCGUUGAUAUGUAAACUCUAGUGUUUGUGUCCUACAUAAAGCGAUUUGUGGUAUGCAAGGACAUAUACAUACCACAUUUUGGGAAGUUCUGUUGUAGAUUGUACCAGCUGUAUUCACCAUAUUCUUGGAGAGUCAGAUGAAUAAAUCUACCCGCUUCCAGUCCUUUCCUCCCAUCUCCCUCUCCCACACUAAAGUGAAUUGUGGGGCAUGACACAAGUUGGAGAGAGGCCCCAGGGAGUGUUCCAGGACUGAGGGAAAGGAGGAUUUGUGGCUACUCUGUGCCCUGCCAAUGGAAGUAAAAAUAGACCUACCUCCUGGGGUUAUUGUUAAGUUUCAGUGAGCCAGUGCAUACGGACUUUGCUUAUUAGCACAAUGCCUGGCCUUCCACUUUUCCUGAUCAUCUAUAGGCACUGGCCCCUUGAAUAACUUCACUCUGUAUGCUGGGUAUACAGUAAUAUUGCCAGCGCUGAAGCAGAAGAUGCAGACACUGUGAAAUGUGCUGUGGUCAACCAAGCUGUCCACAUGCCAGGAGAUUUAUUUCCCAUCUCUUCAGCAAGCUCUCUCCAUCCUGGGUGGCAUAGAGUAGAAGCUGAGAGUGUGGGCUCUGGACGCCGACAGCAUGGCUUCCAAUCCUGGCCUGUCCGUCACGUGUAGUUGAUUUGUCUUCAGCGAAGCGGAAGUUUGCAGAUUCCUUAAAUGAAUUUAAAUUUCAGUGCAUAGGAGAUGCAGAAACAGAUGAUGAGAUGUGUAUAGCAAGAUCUUUGCAGGAGUUUGCCACUGUCCUCAGGAAUCUUGAAGAUGAACGGAUACGGAUGAUUGAGAAUGCCAGCGAGGUGCUCAUCACUCCCUUGGAGAAGUUUCGAAAGGAACAGAUCGGGGCUGCCAAGGAAGCCAAAAAGAAGUAUGACAAAGAGACAGAAAAGUAUUGUGGCAUCUUAGAAAAACACUUGAAUUUGUCUUCCAAAAAGAAAGAAUCUCAGCUUCAGGAGGCAGACAGCCAAGUGGACCUGGUCCGGCAGCAUUUCUAUGAAGUAUCCCUGGAAUAUGUCUUCAAGGUGCAGGAAGUCCAAGAGAGAAAGAUGUUUGAGUUUGUGGAGCCUCUGCUGGCCUUCCUGCAAGGACUCUUCACUUUCUAUCACCAUGGUUACGAACUGGCCAAGGAUUUCGGGGACUUCAAGACACAGUUAACCAUUAGCAUACAGAACACAAGAAAUCGCUUUGAAGGCACUAGAUCAGAAGUGGAAUCACUGAUGAAAAAGAUGAAGGAGAAUCCCCUUGAGCACAAGACCAUCAGUCCCUACACCAUGGAGGGAUACCUCUACGUGCAGGAGAAACGUCACUUUGGAACUUCUUGGGUGAAGCACUACUGUACAUAUCAACGGGAUUCCAAACAAAUCACCAUGGUACCAUUUGACCAAAAGUCAGGAGGAAAAGGGGGAGAAGAUGAAUCAGUUAUCCUCAAAUCCUGCACACGGCGGAAAACAGACUCCAUUGAGAAGAGGUUUUGCUUUGAUGUGGAAGCAGUAGACAGGCCAGGGGUUAUCACCAUGCAAGCUUUGUCGGAAGAGGACCGGAGGCUCUGGAUGGAAGCCAUGGAUGGCCGGGAACCUGUCUACAACUCGAACAAAGACAGCCAGAGUGAAGGGACUGCGCAGUUGGACAGCAUUGGCUUCAGCAUAAUCAGGAAAUGCAUCCAUGCUGUGGAAACCAGAGGGAUCAACGAGCAAGGGCUGUAUCGAAUUGUGGGUGUCAACUCCAGAGUGCAGAAGUUGCUGAGUGUCCUGAUGGACCCCAAGACUGCUUCUGAGACAGAAACAGAUAUCUGUGCUGAAUGGGAGAUAAAGACCAUCACUAGUGCUCUGAAGACCUACCUAAGAAUGCUUCCAGGACCACUCAUGAUGUACCAGUUUCAAAGAAGUUUCAUCAAAGCAGCAAAACUGGAGAACCAGGAGUCUCGGGUCUCUGAAAUCCACAGCCUUGUUCAUCGGCUCCCAGAGAAAAAUCGGCAGAUGUUACAGCUGCUCAUGAACCACUUGGCAAAUGUUGCUAACAACCACAAGCAGAAUUUGAUGACGGUGGCAAACCUUGGUGUGGUGUUUGGACCCACUCUGCUGAGGCCUCAGGAAGAAACAGUAGCAGCCAUCAUGGACAUCAAAUUUCAGAACAUUGUCAUUGAGAUCCUAAUAGAAAACCACGAAAAGAUAUUUAACACCGUGCCCGAUAUGCCUCUCACCAAUGCCCAGCUGCACCUGUCUCGGAAGAAGAGCAGUGACUCCAAGCCCCCGUCCUGCAGCGAGAGGCCCCUGACGCUCUUCCACACCGUUCAGUCAACAGAGAAACAGGAACAAAGGAACAGCAUCAUCAACUCCAGUUUGGAAUCUGUCUCAUCAAAUCCAAACAGCAUCCUUAAUUCCAGCAGCAGCUUACAGCCCAACAUGAACUCCAGUGACCCAGACCUGGCUGUGGUCAAACCCACCCGGCCCAACUCACUCCCCCCGAAUCCAAGCCCAACUUCACCCCUCUCGCCAUCUUGGCCCAUGUUCUCGGCGCCAUCCAGCCCUAUGCCCACCUCAUCCACGUCCAGCGACUCAUCCCCCGUCAGGUCUGUUGCAGGGUUUGUUUGGUUUUCUGUUGCUGCCGUUGUUCUCUCAUUGGCUCGGUCCUCUCUUCAUGCAGUGUUCAGCCUCCUCGUCAACUUUGUUCCCUGCCAUCCAAACCUGCACUUGCUUUUUGACAGGCCAGAAGAAGCGGUACAUGAAGACUCCAGCACACCGUUCCGGAAGGCAAAAGCCUUGUAUGCCUGCAAAGCUGAACAUGACUCAGAACUUUCGUUCACAGCAGGCACGGUCUUCGAUAACGCAGAGUGUCCUUCAGCUUCCACAGCCAUCUUCACUGCCACACCGAAGCUCCGGGCACCUCCACCUCUCACCUGGGCACUUCCACUGGCCGCCUGACACAUCUUCUCACAUCUGCUCUUGCUGCCAUAACCCCCUCUUUACAGAGCAGCGAGAGUGAUCUUUGAAAAACGGAAAUGGCAUUAAAGCCCUUCAGUGGCCUCCCAUUGCUCUGAGAAUUACUUACAAGGCCCUCCAGGGCCCAGUUCCUGCCCCUCUGACCUCACGCCCUCACUUGACAUACUACAGCCUCAUGCCUUCUUCAUGUUCUCAAGCAAGGUCGGCAAACUAUGACCUGCCCGUCAAAUCCAACCUGCCACCUGUCACCUAACAAUUCUGUAACUGCUCCCACAUACAACAUGGUCGUCAUCAUAAAUCCUAUAGGUAUUGUUGAGAGCAGGAGGAAAGUUUGGUUGAGUGAGUGAGAGACCUUACCCAAGCCUUCCUGUGGUCUCUAGGAGUCAUGGCAGAGUUCGCUGACACUGGUCUGCUUUUAACCAGCCUUGCCAGUGACCUUUCAAAUUCCCUGAGGAGCAAAAGGCCAAAUUGAACCUGAAAGAAAACACCUCUCAGUGUUGACUGAGUUGCAGUAGAAAAUGGACCUGAC